GCAGACUCAGAACAGCACUACUCACAGCAGGGCCUCUUGCUCGCUCUAGCUGCUGGGAGGAAAACGGCUUGCUAAUCUCCACGCCCAGAAAUUCAGACAAGAGCAUUCUCCUUAUCUCAUCUGCACAGGAAGCAGGUCUAAGUGUAAUUUCACAAGCCCCUGACUCUGUGUAGACACCCAGCUCUCCAGAAAAAUGCUUUGAAGACAAAGGAUACAGCAUACAGUCCCGUGUCUCGGCUGAGUCAUCGCAUUCCUUAAUAGUGUCUUCUCCCCGGGUUUGGUGGCCUGCUUCUGGAGUGGUCAGUUCUGCUGCCGACAUGCCCACCCAGCUCGAGAUGGCCAUGGACACCAUGAUUAGAAUCUUCCACCGCUAUUCUGGCAAGGAAAGGAAGAGAUUCAAGCUCAGCAAGGGGGAACUGAAACUGCUCCUGCAGCGAGAGCUCACGGAAUUCCUCUCGUGCCAAAAGGAAACCCAGUUGGUUGAUAAGAUAGUGCAGGACCUGGAUGCCAAUAAGGACAACGAAGUGGAUUUUAAUGAAUUCGUGGUCAUGGUGGCAGCUCUGACAGUUGCUUGUAAUGAUUACUUUGUAGAACAAUUGAAGAAGAAAGGAAAAUAAAGAGGAGGCAGCAAUGGGAACCAUCAUGGAAGCAGAGAGCAGCCCUCACCUGACACUGAAUCUGCUGGUGUCUUGAUCUUGGACUUCCCAGACUUCAGAACAGUGAGAAUUUAAAUUUCUAUUGUUUAUAAAUUACCCAGUGUGUGGUAUUUUGUUAUAGCAACACAGACUAAGACAAUAAGCUCUAGGAGUUGUCAAAUGCCUAUAUAUUUUGUUGGGGUCUCCUGGAGGGAUUUCCAACGCAUCCACCCUAUUUGCCCUUUGUGGCCCCAUGAGUCAUCCUUUCAUGAAGUGAAAAGAUACAUCUCUUAUAGUCAUGCCAUAUUUUUCAUUCCAAGUUUUACGGUUUAUGUCAAUAUGUAUUAUGUAUGAAAAACAAACUAGCUUUUUGUCAAAUGCUGCCAAAAUGUAGCAUCUCAAUGUCUGGCAUAAGAAAAGAAAGACACAAAUGGUGAUUGUGAUGCUGGCAAACCAAUGCACAACGUAGCCAAAAUACAUGUCAUAUUUAAUGUGGGACUAAAAACUCACCUUCAGGAAGACUUUCACCUUGAAAUCUGGUGAUGUGUGGAACAGAUGUUUUAAUUUAGCUAAAAUUAUUUGCAUAAUCGAUUUAACACAUGGUUUAUCAAACCUGCCAAAGAGCAGGUGACAAUAUGGAAUUAAUAUGAUUACUAAUUUGACACAUCAUUGAGAUUAAUUUGACCUUUCUCGAUCUCAGAAUACCUAGAGGUCUUCACAGACAGGAAUAGUGUGCUAUGAAAUGCAGUCUAAAAUCCACCAUCUUAGCAUCAUAAAGUAAGCAACCACUUUGCUCAGUCUGGCCUCAUGUUUCUAUUCCUUUUCUUUCCAUCUCUUCUCUAAAUGGAAAGGAAGGCAAUGAGUGAAUAUUGGGGAACAUAUCUGAUUCACAGUGUUCAAAAUUUUAUGAAAAGUAAUUGAUCUAACGUGCCUCUGAUACUAGAUGUGGUACUGCCUUCUCCCUGGUCUGUUGAUUUAUCCUUGAAUCUAGACUCAAAGGAUAUCACCUUUGAGAAUUAAUUGGCUUAAGCCUUUAGCUUUAAGUCUAAAGACUCAAAAUAAUGACUUUUUUUUUUUUUUGCGAUGGAGUUUCACUCUUGUCACCAGUUGUCACCCAGGCUGAAGUGCAAUGGCAUGAUCUCGGCUCACUGCCACCUCCACGUCCUGGGUUCAAGCAAUUUUCCUGCCUCAGCCUCCCAAGUAGCUGGGAAUACAGGUGCACACCACCACACCGGGCUAAUUUUUGUAUUUUUAGUAGAGAUGGGGUUUCACCAUGUUGGCCAGGAUGGUCUUGAACUCCUGAUCUCAGGUGAUCUGCCCACCUCGGCGUCCCCAAGUACUGGGAUUACAGGCGUGAGCCACCGUGCCCGGCCAAAAUAAUGACUUUUAAAUUGUAUAUCAGUUUGAUUACAAUAGUAAAUUAUUCUAUUAGAAAUAAUAGAAAUGUUUAUUAAUAGGGAAUUGAUAAAAUAAAAUAAUAUCGUAUGCGAGUAAAAUGCUGUGUGCCCAUUUAAAUGAUGUGGAAAAAGUAUAUUUAAUGAUAUAAAAACAUGUUUGUGAUAUGUGACAUGAAGAAAUCAUAUUGCAUCUCUGAAAAAUAACAAUAAAAACGAGAAAUCAUAUUGCAAA